GAGCGCCACCGGGAGGGCUACGCGGCGGCCGCAGCCAUGGGUGCUGGGCCUGCGGGGGCGCGGGGGGUGCGCGAGGACCUGCGGGGCGGGGCGGGAGAGAAGGCUGCCGGGACCGGCCCUAGACACUGAGCCGCGGUGGGAUCCCCACCGGCUCUGCGAGGCCCUGCGAGCGCCAGGGAGGCGCCACGAGGGAGCCGGGCAGCCGCGGGCCACUUCAGGGGGGCCCGCCUCGCCGCCCGGGCGGUCGAGAGAUCCUUGGGGGCACAUCUCGGGGUGCGGUGACCCGCCCGGCGCAUUUCGGGGGUCGGGGCGCAAUUGCCAGGGGACAUCUGGAGCCCGGCCCUGCUUCUGUCGGGCUCCAGGGUACCCCUGGAUGGCUGCGCUGUGCCCUCGCCGGCCGCCCGGGCGCCGCAGCGGCUGAGUUCGCCGGGAUCGCCGGGCCGCCGCCCUUGCCACCCGCUGCAUGCUCGGCGCCCGGGUCGCGGCCCACCUGGACGCACUGGGCCCCCUGGUCCCCUACGUGCCGCCGCCGCUGCUGCCCUCUAUGUUCUACGUGGGCCUGUUCUUCGUCAAUGUGCUGAUCCUGUACUACGCCUUCCUCAUGGAGUACAUCGUCCUCAACGUGGGCCUCGUCUUCCUGCCCGAGGACAUGGACCAGGCGCUCGUGGACCUCGGCGUGCUCUCCGACCCCGGCUCGGGCCUUUACGAUGCUGACUCGGAGCUCGACGUCUUUGAUGCGUACUUGGAGUAGGGUCUCGACUGCUGUUCCCCUCUUCCCUACACGAUCCGCAACCCAUGCCCUGGACCAGCCGCCCAGAUCAUGCCGCCGCAGCUGGUUGGGGGCACCAUCUGGACGGGGAUGGUUCCCCAGGAGGAGACCCUCCCCUGCCUCCGAGGCCUACCUGCUCCCCUCAAAAGCUUCGUGCCAACAGAGAGGUUCCUGUUUGAACCCAGGAGAGUGGAAGAGAGAUUGGGACUGAGUGCUGAGGUUGGGAAGGCACCUGCUCCCACAGAAGGGGGAACGCAAGAGGCAUCCCAAGACCUCAUCUGCCUGCAGUGUCAAAUCGAUGGCCUGGCCUUGGCUUCUGAUUAUUUGCAGCUGCGAUGGAUGUUUACAGGAACCCAGCCAGAGUUUGCCUCCCUGCACUUCAUCCCGGAGCGCACCUGCUUCCCCCACUUCACCUUCGGAGAGGACACUUCAAACUGCGGACACACGCAAAAGCGACUCCCAGCUCCGUUUGAUGUGAGUUGAGCCUUCAGGCCAGCUGGGUUUAGCCCGAGGCUGGUCUUAGAUGCAGCGACUGUUUCAGGGGUGACUCAGAAGAAAAAGAAGCUGAGGAAGCUGUUGGGGGGCUGAGGGUGGGAUUCUCGCUCCUUCAUUUCAGGUUACUCGUUCUUCAGCAAGUUGGCAAAACAGACAUCAUGCUGGUGAGUGCCACGUUACUCCCCUGGCUGGAAAUGCUUUUCUGAAAGUAUGAGUGUUGUGCCUACUUAAUUCUGAUAAACCUGUCUAAGCAAUACUUAGGAGGCUUACUUCUUUGGAUUAAAAAAAAAUGUAUGCAACUCCAA